UUUAUGUCCCGCUCAGCCCUCCAAGGCCAACCUCCAAGCUUAUCAAAACCUCAUGCAAAGCACGUGCUGAUGGGCUGGGAAGUCCUGCGUGAGCCCUGAAGGUGGCUCUGAGGGGCUUCCCUCAUCCCUUUGCUCCCAGGCGGGCCCCACGGGGUGCAGGUUCUCAGAUGACUCUCUGAGGUGUGUGAAUAAGGGUCUCUGUUCAGGCGCGUCCCCACAGGAGAUGAGACCACAGAACGCAGCCCUGAGUUUGAAGCAUCCCAGAAGGUUCUUUCUCUCUGACCCGCACACCCACCACUGUUCUGGGUGCUCACAAAACCCACCAUUGCUUCUGGUAAUUUCUCAGCUGCUCCUCCUGUCCAGCGACCCCUGCUGCAGAGGCCCAGGGGAAACACAGACCAGGCCUGUGAGAAGCUCCUGUUUCAGACAAAGAAAUGGUGUCAGCGAUAAAACUGGAAACUGUUCCCAGCUCGACACCUGACCUGGCCCUUCCACCCCCAGGAUCCUGCCCCCAGGCGGCCCUUCCACCCCCAGGAUCCUGCCCCCACGCGGCCCAGCCCCCACCAGGAUCCUGCCCCUGCAUCCUCCGCUGGGUUGGCAUCUGCAUUUUUGGUGCCUUCCAGGGAAAGGGCAACAUGGCUGACAAGGCCAAGCCUGCCAAAGCUGCCAACAGGACGCCCCCCAAGUCCCCGGGGGACCCCUCGAAGGACCGGGCAGCCAAGAGGCUGUCGCUGGAAUCGGAGGGUGCUGGUGAGGGGGCAGCCGCAUCCCCUGAGCUCAGUGCCCUGGAGGAGGCCUUCCGGCGCUUUGCCGUGCACGGGGACGCCAGGGCCACCGGGAGGGAGAUGCACGGCAAGAACUGGUCGAAGCUGUGCAAGGACUGCCAGGUGAUCGACGGCAGGAACGUGACCGUCACUGACGUGGACAUCGUCUUCAGCAAGAUCAAAGGGAAGUCUUGCCGGACCAUCACCUUUGAGCAGUUCCAGGAGGCGCUGGAGGAGCUCGCCAAGAAGCGAUUCAAAGACAAGAGCAGCGAGGAGGCCGUUCGCGAGGUGCACAGGCUCAUCGAGGGCAAGGCGCCCAUCAUCUCAGGGGUGACGAAAGCCAUCUCGUCGCCCACAGUGUCGAGGCUCACGGACACCACCAAGUUCACGGGCUCCCACAAGGAGCGCUUCGACCCCUCUGGCAAGGGCAAGGGCAAGGCUGGCCGCGUGGAUCUGGUGGACGAGUCAGGCUAUGUGUCCGGCUACAAGCACGCAGGCACCUACGACCAGAAGGUGCAAGGGGGCAAGUAGCCCCCGCUCCAUGCCUCGCGGCACUGCCGGUGUCCCCAGAGCAGGGACUCUGUCACCUCGCACUUCAUUACAUUCCUGUACUAACUGGGGCAGAACUCAGACGGGUGCCCCAGAGGGGGCUGGGGGGCGGCCAGGCCCAGGCCUCCCUCCUGCCCCUCCUCCUACCGGAUGCCCCCAGCACUCCCCUCUCAAACCAGGUUUGGGCCCCAGUUCGCUGACCCUCCUAAUACACCUGCCUCGUCCUCAGCCAUUUCCAAAGUGUCUCGCGGAUCACACCACACUGGGCACGUGGUUUGCAGGUCAAAGGGGCGUUUUAAAGCAGCUGGCUGUCAUGGCAACAGGAGGCUGUGCUGACCUCCUGAGCGGCAGACACCUUCCAGGAGCCCUGAGGGUGGCAGGAGCUAACCCCAACCAGCAGGCAACUAACACGGAAUUGGCCCCACACCGGACGUGGGAGGUGUCUGUGGGGCCCGAGGCCUGUCCUGUGUGCAGCGGACACCACGGGGCCUUCCUGCUUUCCUGGGCAGAGGGCAGAGUGAGGCCACCUGGCGGGGGUGCUGGGCGCCUGGCACAUGUGUGGGGAAGCCGGUCACAUGGACACACCUGUGCACACAUGCCUACAGGCCAGCUCUGUGCCAAGGGCAACCUAGGUAAAACGAAAGCCGUCAGGGGCAGUGGGCGGCUUCCCGGCUGACCACAGUGGCUUGGACUGUGAGGGUAGAGUAGGCUCGCUUUGCUUUCCUGAGAAGAUGCGGUGGCUGCCUAUGUUCUCAGAGCGGGUCUGGGAAGAUUCAGAAUGUCCGGUCCCUGUGGUGUUGCCAGGCAAGAGACACGAAGUGCCGAGACACUCCUCGCCUCACCGCGUGACAGAGCCUCUGCCCGGCCCUCCCGUUCGCCCGUCCUCACUAGCUGCACCCUGUUUGCUCGCAGACCUCCCAUUGCCACAGCCCAAGCACCUUCUUCAACUCUCCCAAAAUGGCUCAGCCUAACCUCUCCUGGCCAAUCCCCCCCGCCGGAGAGCAGGACACUAGGGAGGACCCCCAGUCCUGCAGUGUCUGUGGGGGUUUCUCUGCCAGCAGGGGGCUGAGCAGAGCCCAUCCAGGACACUCCACACUGCCAGGACACACCCAGGCGGCCCGCCCUUGCCUGUCUGCACCUGGGGAGAAGCCGGCGCUCCUGCUCCCUCCUGGGGAGGCUGACGGGUGUGGCCACCCGCUGUCACAAUGGCACACUGCCACUGUCCCUUGGCACGCACACAGCCACAGCCACACGUGUGACCUGCUGGGCCGUGGUUCUGGAGUCUACCUGCGGAUGAGCCUGCGGCAGUCCUGGGGAAACUUUUCCAGAGCCUGUUAGCCCGUGGCUACGGUCAGGCUCUGGCCAGGGCAGAGGGCUGCCCAGGGCCAGGCUCACAGUACAGGAGGGUGGCGAGGCCCCUCCCUCACUGGCACGCAUGAGCACCACCCGCCUCCCCGACUCCCAAGAGUGCACCUGCUGCGGCCACAGCUCCGUGGAAGGACUCCCCCUACCUGAGCAGAGCAGAAGCCCCAGGGCGGAGCUCCCAGCCAGCAUGGUCCGCUGAGGGCUGGGGGGCGGUCUCCGAGGCCCCUCAACAGAGAAGCCUCCACCUGAGGAUGGGGAGGACCUGGCAGGCAGCUUCCACGGCAGGGCUGGGAAGUUCAGUGCCUGGAAAUAAAGAGCAAGGAAAAAUGGACCUCAGGCUUCGUGGCUCCUUUAGGAUGUCACCUCACCGGCCUGGGGAAGGCGGGGGGUGCCCAAGCCCAGCCCUGUGCCCCCGCUGAACCUGGCUGGACCGCGUGUGAAAGGCAGAACUAACGUGCGGAAACAUUUGAAAACAACUCUGAAUGUGCGGUUCGGAAUCACCCGAUCACAGACGAGCGGUCACCGGAAUCGCCCGGUCACAGACGAGCAGUCAUCGGACUCACCCGAUCACAGACGAGCGGUCACCGGAAUCGCCCGAUCACAGACGAGCGGCCACCGGAAUCGCCCAAUCACAGACAAGCAGUCAUCGGAAUCACCCGAUCACAGACGAGCAGUCAUCGGACUCACCCGAUCACAGACGAGCGGUCACCAGACUCGCCCGAUCACAGACGAGCAGUCAUCGGAAUCACCCGAUCACAGACGAGCAGUCAUCGGACUCACCCGAUCACAGACGAGCGGUCACCAGAAUCGCCCGAUCACAGACGAGCAGUCAUCGGAAUCACCCGAUCACAGACGAGUGGCCACCGGAAUCACCCGAUAACAGCCCAUCACAACUCCAAAGCCCUUGUGUUGAAAAGGCCGAGGACGAGUGGUCACCAAACAGGGUGGCUCCCCAGGUCCCGAAGCCUGAGACCCGGAAGGCCCUGGCACCCUUACACCCUCGGACUCCUGCCCUCCUCGGCCUCCCUGGCCCCAGCGCGGCUCCACCCUGGGCUGCGUCUCCUGGUCACAGGCUGCGUUUCUCCUUUCUGUCCGUGGGCAGCCCAGUCCCCACAGUCACGGCCAAGCCACGCAGAACGAACAUGACUCCAGAGGACCUCGCCCUGGAGCUGAGCCUGGCGCCGGGUCAGGACGGAGGGAAGGGCGGGUUGGGGUCCGCGGGUCCUCACACCGCACGGCAGGCACAGAGGCUCGCCAGGCCCUGAUCCGGUCUGUGGGGACGAGGGACACUGAGGAGAGGUGCUGGGCACCAGGACGCUGCCUCCUGGUCCCUGGUUGGCCUCAGACAAGCACGGCCUCGAGAAAAGAGCCAAGCGCAUCGGGAGCACACCAGAAACCGGCCCUGAGCACGAGAAGAGCCUCCGCCCGGCCCGGGCACCACCCGACCUCGCAGGGAGCAGGCCCUGUCACCGACGGGUCACCUCGCCCACACGGCCAGCACCGACUCACCACAGCCCUUCCCAGACCUGGCUGGAGUGGCCGGAGCGGCGGGGCUCAUGGCUCCCAUCUUGGCCCCUGGAGGUGAGCUCAUUCACAGAAGUGGUCCCUUCACUCUGAGAGAGAAAAUCGUGGCGUGCAUCCCAAACCCUAGGCCACGCCUGUGGGUUUCGUGAAUGAGAUCGAGGCUGCUGUGGCACCCUGCCCGUCCUGGCCUGGAGCACCCUGGGAUCCUGGAGGGAGAGGCCCCACGCCCCCACUCUCCCUCCACACUUCCAGGGUUGGUGCCCACGAGUUAGAGGCACGCCCUCCCCCAGCGGCCCUCAGGCUUUUCUCAGACAUGCGGGAGCCAGGAGAGCACCCUUCUCCACUCAGCUCCAAAGCGAAUCUUUGAAAACACCCACUCGGCUCCCAUCUCUGUCACCUAGCCAGGAGGGGUAGCAAAAAUAAAGUCACGAGGACAUAGUGGUCACCACUGUCAGUUACAACUUGUCUGUGGAAUCCGUAAUUGCAUCUGUGUGCCGCCUCCGAACACAGAACAUUGUUUGGACGGCAGCCCCACUGCACAUAACAGACCCGUGCAUCUUCCUCAGUCAGUUUCUGAAUAUUGUGAAUUCAGGCAGGUGUGUGUUCUCUUCUGCAUGUUUUUAUGCACUGCCAAUUAGCUUCUACUAACCACGGUUCAACAGAAAAUAAAUGUGUAUUUGUGAAUAACAAACUGCACAACCUGCAAACCAGGAGAGAGGGACAGGUUCUGUCAGGGGUGACACCAGGACACAGGGACAGGUUCUGUCGGGGGUGACACCAGGACACAGGGACAGGUUCUGUCAUGGGUGACACGAGGACACAGGGACAGGUUCUAUCAUGGGUGACACCAGGAGAGAGGGACAGGUUCUGUUGGGGGUGACAAGAGGAGACAGGGACAGGUUCUGUCGGGGGUGACACCAGGAGAGAGGGACAGGUUCUGUCAGGGGUGACACCAGGAGAGAGGGACAGGUUCUGUUGGGGGUGACACCAGGACACAGGAAUAGGUUCUGUCGGGAGGACAGUGCUGAUCGUGUCUCAGCAUCAGGAAAGGAGAAAGGCAGAGGGAGAGCGCUGAGAAGACUGUUCACGCCAGAGUGCUUAUUUAUUUUUAAUUUACUGCUAUAGGAUAAGCAACCAGGUAGUGUUCCUAACAAUUAGCGUUACCAAAAUUAAAGUUCAAAUUAUAUGUUUAAAAUAUUGUAGAAGAUAUAUAUUUAUACUGGACUACUUUUACACCUUCUAAUAUCCUGUCCAAGUUUGGGCGCAGAUGGUGGAGUUGGGCUGGCAUCAUGUCCUGUGGCCGCCCCACUUGCCUGUUGGUGCCACUCCAUCCCGGGCCCCAGGGAUGCCAGCUCAGGGCUGACCACAGCAGCCCUGCGUGGGCAUCACCUCCUACCCCAGCCCCCAUCCUGGGCUGCUGCGGCCGCCUGCUUUUGUGAAUGGUGUUUUGUUGGCACAGGGCCUGUCCUGUGUUUUCACACAGGCCUGUGGCUCCUGCUGUACAAGUGGAGUGGGGAGGAGUUGAGAUGGAGAUGCCUUGGCCCUGGACACUUACCUGUCCCUCUACUGGCCCAGCUCAUCUCCUCCUGUGGGCAAUCACGCGUGCACUGGCCACCCUCCCACCCCACAGCACACACCACGAGGGGAUGGCACAGGGGGAAGAUGAGGCUGGACCGUGAUGUUAUCAAUAGGCUAGAACGUCCUUCAAACACUGAACCUGCAUCUUUCCUCCUCUUACUACUGAACACUUUGUGAGCUCUGGUGGUCCAGGGUGCAGCGUUUGUCCCUGGGCAUGUGAUGGGGAGUCCUGGGCACAUCGAGAUGCUUUACUUCUUUCUUUCGACCUCUUAAAAAACUAAACCAAGCCAAACCACAAAGGAAAUCUGCACAACUUAAGAGAAACUUGAAAGGGAUCGUGUAACUACUAGUUUGUACUAAGUUUUUUUCAAGAAAGGGAAACAAAUUUAUAUAUAUAUAUAUAUAUAUAUAUGUGCAAUAUAUUUUUACACUGUGUGAUUAACAUUAGGGAGUACUGAGUGCAUCACUUUAUCAGUGUGACGGGUGAUGUCCACGUCAUGGCUGUUCUGACUCUGAAAGCCACUUCUGCUGAUGUCUAAACCGCACUCACCGCGGACGUCCGCGGGGUGGGGUGGCCCUGCUGUUCCUCCUGCAGGUGAGAGGUGUGGUGUUGCCUGUUGGACUUGCUGUUGAGCCUGGCUUGCAAACCUGUAGUGAAACAGCUCGUGUCUGUGUGCACACUGCUCCUGUGUCUGCUGUCGUUAACAUUGUGUGUCAAGUUGGUAAAGUGACAAAUAAAGGUGUUAAAACAUGGA